GUCACCACCUCCCGCAAGUGCCAGAGCCGAGCGGACUGCGCGGAGGCUGCGGAGCCGGCGGCCGCGGGAGCUGACCCUGCGGGGUCCCGGGGGGGGAGGGGGAGCCGCGAAGCCCCCACUGAGGCCGCCGCUGCCGGGCCUCCCCUCCCCCCCGGGCGGGCGCCAUGCGGGGGAGCCCGGGCGACGCGGAGCGGCGGCAGCGCUGGGGUCGCCUGUUCGAGGAGCUGGACAGUAACAAGGAUGGCCGCGUGGACGUGCACGAGUUGCGCCAGGGGCUGGCCAGGCUGGGCGGGGGCAACCCAGACCCCGGCGCCCAACAGGGUAUCUCCUCUGAGGGUGAUGCUGACCCAGAUGGCGGGCUCGACCUGGAGGAAUUUUCCCGCUAUCUGCAGGAGCGGGAACAGCGUCUGCUGCUCAUGUUUCACAGUCUUGACCGGAACCAGGAUGGUCACAUUGAUGUCUCUGAGAUCCAACAGAGUUUCCGAGCUCUGGGCAUUUCCAUCUCGCUGGAGCAGGCUGAGAAAAUUUUGCACAGCAUGGACCGAGACGGCACAAUGACCAUUGACUGGCAAGAAUGGCGCGACCACUUCCUGUUGCAUUCGCUGGAAAAUGUGGAGGACGUGCUGUAUUUCUGGAAGCAUUCCACGGUCCUGGACAUUGGCGAGUGCCUGACAGUGCCGGACGAGUUCUCAAAGCAAGAGAAGCUGACGGGCAUGUGGUGGAAACAGCUGGUGGCCGGCGCAGUGGCAGGUGCCGUGUCACGGACAGGCACGGCCCCUCUGGACCGCCUCAAGGUCUUCAUGCAGGUCCAUGCCUCAAAGACCAACCGGCUGAACAUCCUUGGGGGGCUUCGAAGCAUGGUCCUUGAGGGAGGCAUCCGCUCCCUGUGGCGCGGCAAUGGUAUUAAUGUACUCAAGAUUGCCCCCGAGUCAGCUAUCAAGUUCAUGGCCUAUGAACAGAUCAAGAGGGCCAUCCUGGGGCAGCAGGAGACACUGCAUGUGCAGGAGCGCUUCGUGGCUGGCUCCCUGGCUGGUGCCACAGCCCAAACCAUCAUUUACCCUAUGGAGGUGCUGAAGACGCGGCUGACCUUGCGCCGGACGGGCCAGUAUAAGGGGCUGCUGGACUGCGCCAGGCGUAUCCUGGAGAGGGAGGGGCCCCGUGCCUUCUACCGCGGCUACCUCCCCAACGUGCUGGGCAUCAUCCCCUAUGCGGGCAUCGACCUGGCCGUCUACGAGACUCUGAAGAACUGGUGGCUUCAGCAGUACAGCCACGACUCGGCAGACCCAGGCAUCCUCGUGCUCCUGGCCUGCGGUACCAUAUCCAGCACCUGCGGCCAGAUAGCCAGUUACCCGCUGGCCCUGGUCCGGACCCGCAUGCAGGCACAAGCCUCCAUCGAGGGUGGCCCCCAGCUGUCCAUGCUGGGUCUGCUACGUCACAUCCUGUCCCAGGAGGGCAUGCGGGGCCUCUACCGGGGGAUCGCCCCCAACUUCAUGAAGGUUAUUCCAGCUGUGAGCAUCUCCUAUGUGGUCUACGAGAACAUGAAGCAGGCCUUGGGGGUCACGUCCAGGUGAGGGACCCGGAGCCCGUCCCCCCAAUCCCUCACCCCCCACACCUCAGCCACUGGAGACUGAUGAUCCAACCACAGGAUCCCUACUCUUUGGCCACGAGAUCCCAGUACCCAGAUCCUGGAUCCUAGACUCCUAUGCCCCAACCAUUGGGUCAUGGGAUCCCAGCAUCCAGAUCCUGGAUCCUAGACUCCUAUGCCCCAACCACUGGGUCAUGCGAUCCCCACCCUUCAGCCACUAGAUCCCAGAUCCCCCUGUAACCAUAACUGUGGAUCCCUUACUUCAGCAACUCAAGUCUGCUACCCUAACCACAAGAUUCAAGAUUAUCCACACCCCAGCCCUUAAUCCCCAUCCCCCAAAUCACUGGAUCCUGCAGCCCCACAUCCUAAGGUGGAUCCCACGCUUCCCUGUGCCCCCUACUGGAUCCUGGACCUCUACGUCUUAACCACUGGAUCCCACACAAAUCAGUGAAUGGAUCCCAACACCCCAACCACAGGAGCACGGAUUCCCUGUACCUCAACACCCAGACCCUGCCUCCCUCAGGCACCAGAUCCAGUGUCCUAGUGAAACGCUGGAUCCUAGAUCCCCAACCCCAGAUCCCCAUGCCUCGAGCCCUGGAUCUCCAAGCUCAGCUGCUGGAUUCUGGAUGUCAACAAACCUCACCACUGGAUCCUGACAACCACAAUGCCUGGAUCCUGGGGCCCCCAUCACUGGAUCCCAGAUCCCCUCACUCCACCCACUGGAUUCCUGCAUUGGUUUUUGGUUUUUUGUUUUUUUUUAACCUCGACACUGGGUCUCAGAUCCUUCUGCUGACUGCCAGAUCCCUGCAUUUCAAGCACUACGCCUUCCACCCCCAGGCACUGGAUCCCAGAUUCCCAAGCCUUCACCCACCAGAUUCUGGCUCCUAAAACAAGUGCGGGGGCCCCAGUGGCACAGCAAGUGGAUCCUGGCAACUGCAGCUGCUGGAUUCCAGAUUCUGGGUCCCCAAUCCCUCUGCCCAGUCCCUCAAUGUUGAAACCUCAUCUCUUGAAGGCAGAUCCUGAUAUUCCAAGGCACUGAAUCCCAAGCCCUGAAUCCCCGGUUUCUGAUCUGAAUCUUCCAGGCGCCGGGUCCCAAAUGUUCAGGCCCCAAGUCUAGAUCCUGGCAGCCCAGUCACAGAGUAUCCCACACACACUGGUGCCCAGAGCCGGCUUCUCAUGACAUGAAAUUGCAUGGUCGAGGGAGUCUGUGGGGAAGGAAGCCCAGGUCCUGGCUGCAACCUGCACGGAUGCUGGAUUCCCCCUCACCCCACCUCUGCAUGGCCACCCCCUCCCAGCCCUGUGGGGAAACUGUUCCCUGGAACCACUCCACUCCCUGCAUCCCCACACUUCACAGCAUCUUCCAUCCCCCUCCCACCUUCUAGGCGAAUAGUCCCCAGAGCUGUGUUCCUCCAAGGGGUCCGAGGAAUCACUCACUCCUGGAGGCUGGCAAGGAGACAGUCUGAGGCCAGGGACACAUGAAGGGAUGUCCCCACCCCAGCACUAUCAGGGCCUCCCCAGGCUUCCAGAGUUGAAAGCCAGGAGAAAAUCGGCAAAGACCACCCUUCCCUAAACCCAAGCACCCAAUGAUGCAAAAAACAAAAACAAAAAAAAACCACCAAAUCCCCAAAUUCAUUCCAGAUCUAUUUUUCUACCAGAGAGAGGAGCAAAGUCCUCCUCCCCUGCGCCCUUACAUUCUGCACUUCAUAGUUGGAUUCUGAGCUUAGGAUCAUCUGGAGACCCCAUGGAGGGACUUGGAAAGGGGAACUGGGAUUUGGGGAGGGGCUGGAGGACUUCCGCACGCUUCCACCUCCUUCGACCUCCACUGCGCCCCACCUCCCUGCCUGUGUGUGUUAUUUCAAAGGAAAAGAACAAAAGGAAUAAAUUUUCUAAGCUCUUU